CGGCUGUGAACCAUCAUGGGUGGGGCUGCCUUUUCUCAGCCCAGCAGGUCCCCAGCUGCUUGGAAAGGCCCCAGUGAUUACAUGAGGGUCACCUGGGUCAUGUAGGACGGGCUCCUCCUCUCAAAAUGAGAAGACUCACAGCCUUCAUUCCCCUUGCCGCGUAGCAUGGUGCUCACGGGCUCCAGAAGUUACAGCGUGGACAUCUUUUUUUUUUUUUUUUUUUUUGAGAUGGAAUCUCACUCUGUUGCCCAGGCUGGAGUGCAGUAGCGUGAUCUUGGCUCACUGCAACCUCCGCCUCCUGGGUUCAAGCAAUUCUCCUGCCUCAGUCUCCCGAGUAGCUGGGAUUACAGGCGCACGCCACCACGCCCGGCUGAUUUUUAGUAGAGAUGGAGUUUCGCCAUGUUGGCCAGGCUGGUCUCGAACUCCUGACCUCAGGUGAUCCGCCCAUCCAGGCCUCCCAAAGUGCUGGGAUUACAGGUGUGAGCCACUGUGCCCCGCGGAGCAUGGACACCUUCUGCCCACCACGUGAGCCCGGGAUCCUGCGGCUCAGAGCUGCCAGCAGCUUCUCCAAGGCACGGGAGGAAGAAAUUACCCCUGUGGUCUCCAUUGCCUACAAAGUCCUGGAAGUUUUCCCCAAAGGCCGCUGGGUGCUCAUAACCUGCUGUGCACCCCAGCCACCACCGCCCAUCACCUAUUCCCUCUGUGGAACCAAGAACAUCAAGGUGGCCAAGAAGGUGGUGAAGACCCACGAGCCGGCCUCCUUCAACCUCAACGUCACACUCAAGUCCAGUCCAGACCUGCUCACCUACUUCUGCUGGGCGUCCUCCACCUCAGGUGCCCAUGUGGACAGUGCCAGGCUACAGAUGCACUGGGAGCUGUGGUCCAAGCCAGUGUCUGAGCUGCGGGCCAACUUCACUCUGCAGGACAGAGGGGCAGGCCCCAGGGUGGAGAUGAUCUGCCAGGCGUCCUCGGGCAGCCCACCUAUCACCAACAGCCUGAUCGGGAAGGAUGGGCAGGUCCACCUGCAGCAGAGACCAUGCCACAGGCAGCCUGCCAACUUCUCCUUCCUGCCGAGCCAGACAUCGGACUGGUUCUGGUGCCAGGCUGCAAACAACGCCAAUGUCCAGCACAGCGCCCUCACAGUGGUGCCCCCAGGAGGGUUGCCCAGGGCACCCACCAUCGUGCUGGUUGGCAGCCUUGCCUCCACUGCGGCCAUCACCUCCAGGAUGCUGGGCUGGACCACGUGGGCCAGGUGGUGACCAGAAGAUGGAGGACUGGCAGGGUCCCCUGGAGAGCCCCAUCCUUGCCUUGCCGCUCUACAGGAGCACCCGCCGUCUGAGUGAAGAGGAGUUUGGGGGGUUCAGGAUAGGGAAUGGGGAGGUCAGAGGACGCAAAGCAGCAGCCAUGUAGAAUGAACCGUCCAGAGAGCCAAGCACGGCAGAGGACUGCAGGCCAUCAGCGUGCACUGUUCGUAUUUGGAGUUCAUGCAAAAUGAGUGUGUUUUAGCUGCUCUUGCCACAAAAAAAAAAAAAAAAAAAAAAGGGUAACUAUGAGAGAUGGUGGAUAUGUUAACUUGCUUCGCUAUAGGAACCUUUGUGCUAUCUAUAUUAUCUAUAUGAAUCCCAUCAUAUCAGGUUGUCUACCUUAAAUAUACACAAAAA